CCCUACCCCUGGAAAGUAAUAUACUGAAGUCUCAUCAUACUGUUUUGGGGAUUCCAGUAAUUAAAAUCUCUAGUGAAUAAAGACCUGUUUCAAAACAACCUGUGAGCUGACUGGACUAUUUAAAGUAAUUCUCCUUGUAGUCACUUUCAGAGUGAAGACAAUGACGAAUACUGUCUUUUACAAAGGGACUUUUUAUUCCACCAACAAAUUCUGGAUUUUGGCAUCAGGAAAACCACUGUUCAAUUUCCAACACUAUAUCCAAGUUGUUUGAGAAAUUAUUUAAAACUCUUUAACUUAGAGGGUUUUCUUUCUCCUUUACUUGUUAAAGUGACUAUAUUACAGAGUCACUUUAAGGAUUAAAUUUAUUGCAUGCAAAGUUUCUAGAUCACUGUCUAGAAGUCAGUUAGAGUAAGUUCUUUAGUUGUCAAUCAAGCAUUUAGUAAGGCCCUGCUUUGUGCCCAGUGUUGACCUCAACAAAGUUGGGGAUAUCAGAAUAUUCUAAGAUACAGUCGUUGUUCCCAAGAAUCUUGUCUUUCACAUACAAGAGGUGUUGCGUUUCAUUUUGCGGCUAAUGUCCAAACGCUGGCCUCAGCCAUUUCACCUUGAAGAUUGCAGUUGGCUUCCAACUGGCCUCUAAACUCUAAUCUAGCAUUUUCCAGUCCAUUGUGACAAAGUCUGCCUUCCCCAGCUACUCCCAGCUGUUGGACCUGCUGCCUUAGAACCACAGAUUGAGACCUCCCUGUCCCCUCUGUCAGACCAGACCAGGGCAGGCAGUAUAUUUGCAUGACGCAGGAUGAUUGACACUGGUGAUUUCACCCAGCUCCCUUCAUAGCAAUUUUGACAACUGCUUCAUCUGAGAGACAUUUGGAAGCAGCAUAGUUUAUGGUGAAGUUCUGGAGUCUCGCUCGGUACAAGCCAGUUUCCACCAUUUACUAGCUCUGUGAUACUGGGCAGUCGUUAGAAAGAAUGCCCGUUCUGGGACAUCAAAACCUAAUAAUUAUUAUUCUCUAAUAGCUAACAUGCAUUAUGUGUGUUUAUUUGCUGUGGCAAAUACUAUGUUGAAAAAAACUUUAGACUUACAGAAAAGUUGCAGUAUUACAGGCAGUUCACACAUGCUCUCUACCUGGCUUCCUCUAACAGUAACAUAUUACAGAAUUAGUAUAUUCAUCAAAAUGAGAAAACAAACCUUUGUCCAAUACUGGUCACAACUUUCUCAUCUUGAUUGAAUUUCAAAUUUGAUGUUUUUCCCCAGAAUUUUUUCAGCAGAUCAUUGAGUACACAGAGGAAUACCGCCACAUGCCGCUGCUGAAGCUCUGGGUCGGGCCAGUGCCCAUGGUGGCCCUUUAUAAUGCAGAAAAUGUGGAGUACUGGAAACAAAUGGCGCUCCAGGAGAAAGAUGUUAACACCCACUUUCCAUUUUACCAUUCUGGAAGAUUUCUUAGAUAUCAUGAAUGAACAAGCAAAUAUAUUGGUUAAGAAACUUGAAAAACACAUUAACCAAGAAGCAUUUAACUGCUUUUUUUACAUCACUCUUUGUGCCUUAGAUAUCAUCUGUGAAACAGCUAUGGGGAAGAAUAUUGGUGCUCAAAGUAAUGAUGAUUCCGAGUAUGUCCGUGCAGUUUAUAGAAUGAGUGAGAUGAUAUUUCGAAGAAUAAAGAUGCCCUGGCUUUGGCUUGAUCUCUGGUACCUUAUGUUUAAAGAAGGAUGGGAACACAAAAAGAGCCUUCAGAUCCUACAUACUUUUACCAACAGUGUCAUCGCUGAACGGGCCAAUGAAAUGAACGCCAAUGAAGACUGUAGAGGUGAUGGCAGGGGCUCUGCCCCCUCCAAAAAUAAACGCAGGGCCUUUCUUGACUUGCUUUUAAGUGUGACUGAUGACGAAGGGAACAGGCUAAGUCAUGAAGAUAUUCGAGAAGAAGUUGACACCUUCAUGUUUGAGGGGCACGAUACAACUGCAGCUGCAAUAAACUGGUCCUUAUACCUGUUGGGUUCUAACCCAGAAGUCCAGAAAAAAGUGGAUCAUGAAUUGGAUGACGUGUUUGGGAAGUCUGACCGUCCCGCUACAGUAGAAGACCUGAAGAAACUUCGGUAUCUGGAAUGUGUUAUUAAGGAGACCCUUCGCCUUUUUCCUUCUGUUCCUUUAUUUGCCCGUAGUGUUAGUGAAGAUUGUGAAGUGGCAGGUUACAGAGUUCUAAAAGGCACUGAAGCCGUCAUCAUUCCCUAUGCAUUGCACAGAGAUCCGAGAUACUUCCCCAACCCCGAGGAGUUCCAGCCUGAGCGGUUCUUCCCCGAGAAUGCACAAGGGCGCCAUCCAUAUGCCUACGUGCCCUUCUCUGCUGGCCCCAGGAACUGUAUAGGUCAAAAGUUUGCUGUGAUGGAAGAAAAGACCAUUCUUUCGUGCAUCCUGAGGCACUUUUGGAUAGAAUCCAACCAGAAAAGAGAAGAGCUUGGUCUAGAAGGACAGUUGAUUCUUCGUCCAAGUAAUGGCAUCUGGAUCAAGUUGAAGAGGAGAAAUGCAGAUGAACGCUAACUAUAUUAUUGGGUUGUGCCUUUAUCAUGAGAAAGGUCUUUAUUUUAAGAGAUCCUUGUCAUUUACAAUUUACAGAUCAUGAGUUCAAUAUGCUUGAAUCCCCUAGACCUAAUUUUUCCUUGAUCCCACUGAUCUUGACAUCAAGUCUAACAAAGAAAAAGUUUUGAGUUUUGUAUUUUCUUUUUUCUUUUUUCUUUAUUUUUUUUUUUUGAAACCGUGUCUCACUCUGUCGCCCAGGCUGGAGGAGUGCAGUGGUGUGAUCUCAGCUCACUGCAACCUCCACCUCCCAGGUUCAAGCAAUUCUUCUGCCUCAGCCUCCCAAGUAGCUGGGAUUACAGGUGCCUGCCACCAUGCCUGGCUAAUUUUUUUGUAUUUUUAGUAGAAACAGGGUGUCACCAUGUUGGCCAGACUGGUCUCAAACUCCUGACCUCAAGUGAUCCACCUGCCUCAGCCUCCCAAAGUGCUGGGAUUAUAGUCGUGAGCCACCACGCCUGGCCAGAGUUUUUUAUUUUUAUCACCACCAUAGAUGUUACAGUUGGCUGUGGUCACAAAAGUAGUUAAUUGUGUCAGCACCCAAAUAAACAUCUAACAGGUUUCUCAACAGAGGAAUCCACAGUCCAAUUCCACUUCAAUUGAUAGACCCAAAAAAUAUAAUUUAAUCAAAGUUCUAGAGUUUUUGUUUGUUUGUUUGAGAUGGAGUCUUGCUCUGUCGCCCAGGCUGGAACGCAGUGGUGACAUCUCGGCUCACUGCAACCUCCACCUCCCAGGUUCAAGUGAUUCUCCUGCCUCAGCCUCCUGAGUAGCUGGGACUACAGGCGCCUGCCACCACGCCCAGCUAAUUUUUGUAUUUUUAGUAGAGAUGGGGUUUCACCAUGUUGGCCAGGAUGGUCUUGAUCUCUUGACCUCGUGAUCUGCCUGCCUCGGCCUCCCAAAGUGCUGGCAUUACAGGCAUGAGCCACCAUGCCUGGCCCAAAGUUCUAGAAUUUUUUAAAGGUAUUCAUGGUGACUCAGGAAUACACACAUACACACACACACACACACACACACACACACACAUACACACAUAUAAUUUGAAAGAGGUGAGUAUGUACUCUGACUUCAGCUCUCAGGUUUUAAAAAUUAUAUUAGUGGGACCAGUUAUGACAAGAAUAAUCAUUAUAGUACUUUUCAGAUUUUAUAACCUGGAGCAGAUUAUUUUAAGUUGAUUAGUAGGUUCUGUUACAGUUUUUCUUUUGAUCGUGCACUUAUAGUCUUCAUUUAAUUCCUCAUAGAAUCCCAGUCACCUUUAUAUAUCAUAUUAUUGGAAGAGAUUCAUCUUCAUAAUCUCCAGUUUUUUCACAGUGCCUCACAGAGUUAAUCAUGCCUUUUGGAGCUAGAAGGACUUUAGAACUUAUCUAGUUAUGCUCCUUUAUAUUAUAAGUAAGGGAAUAGAAUCAAUAAGACAGUUUCUGCCCAAAGUCAUGUUACCAGUUGGUGACAGAGCUGGAAAUACGUAGAGAUCUAUACCCUUAAAUCUCUCCACUCACAUGCUGAUAUACUUUCUACUACAAUAUGCUAUAGCUUUAUGGAACUCAGGGUGAUGAUCAGACGUGUCAUUAGAACAUGAGUCCUCUGCUUCUGAUUCAGGCAUACUUUUGGGAUUCUUCCAUCUUUAAAGGAAAAAGGAAGCCAUUCAUCUAUAUUUAGUAACCCAGUAAUAUCUCACUUAGUUUAGGGUUAGAUCUUUAGUUAAUUCAACCUUAUAGAUCAUACUUAUGAAGGUGAUAACUGACACGUGUUCACUGAAUUUUAAUUUGAUAGGCAAUACAUCUACCCACUCCAUUAUUUUUUAAAACUUCAUUUAAUAGUUUAAACAAGAUUGGUUUUGUUUUCAAUUUUUAUUCACUCUUCAUAGAAUCACAAUUACCUUUAUAUAUCAUAUGUUAUUGGAAGAGAUUCCUCAGUAAUCUCCAAUCUCUCAUAGUGCCUCACAGGGUUGGUCAAUGGCUUUUGGAACUGGAAGGACCUUAGAACUUAUCUGUUAUGCUCCUGAUAGCCAAUAGCAGAUAGAAGCUUGCAAUCAAGAGGGUAGGACAUGUGUUCUUCAAUGGAUAUCAAAGGAAGAGGUUGCAAACCAAAGCCAUUUGGCAAGCCCUGUAGCCUGGGCCAUUUAAGACAGGGGCGGUCUCAGCCAAAUUGCACCCAUUUAACUAUCCCAAAGAGCCACAGUGCCUACAACCCAGGCCCUAAGUUGAUGAAGAAAAAGUCAAGGAAGGAGGUGAUACAAUUGGAAAUAUUCCCAUCAAAUGGUUAAUCUUAUUUAGAAAAUGGGCAUAUUAGAAAAAGUCCUUCCAAGAUGAUUUUGGAUAAUAAAAGUUGUAUUUGUGGAAAUUGGUAUUAUCUCUGUUUUAUGCACUUACAUUUAUCCCUUACAUUUUGUUUUUAGUGACCCUACAUGACAUUAAAUUUAAAGUAAAACAUUGUUUAAUGUUACCUUUUGGCUUGAGAAUGUCUUUCAGCUCCAGAAUUAUUGUUACUCAUAUUUUAAUCAGUAAGUCAUUUAAGCUAUGACAGAGUAGGAAUUGAGAAAUUAUUUCAUAUGCUACAGUAUUGAAAUGUGGAUGCUGCCUUGUUUUAUAAGAAGAUGAUCAAGGUUUGUGUGCCCAUUACCUUUCCUCUGCCUGAAAGACGUGUCUCAAGAAAAAUAAAUUCUAUUUUAGAUGCAGGUACUGCAUUUUAUUCUAAGAAUUGAUAUCAAUUCAAAACAUAGAAAACUGUAAAAGAUAAAUCAGGAGAUGGCUGAUUCAUAAUGGGUAAUAAAAUAAAUAGCACUUUCGAGCUGA